GGCUGGCCCUGGCCUUCCACGACGGCAGCGUCCACAUCGUGCACCGGCUCUCACUGCAGACCAUGGCCGUCUUCUACAGCUCCGCGGCCCCGAGGCCUGUGGAUGAGCCGGCCAUGAAGCGCCCCCGCACCGCGGGCCCCGCCGUCCACUUAAAGGCUAUGCAGCUAUCGUGGACGUCACUGGCCCUGGUGGGGAUUGACAGCCACGGGAAGCUGAGCGUGCUCCGCCUCUCACCUUCCAUGGGCCACCCGCUGGAGGUGGGGCUGGCGCUGCGGCACCUGCUCUUCCUGCUGGAGUACUGCAUGGUGACCGGCUACGACUGGUGGGACAUCCUGCUGCACGUGCAGCCCAGUAUGGUACAGAGCCUGGUGGAGAAGCUGCACGAGGAGUACACGCGCCAGACCGCUGCCCUGCAGCAGGUCCUCUCCACCCGGAUCCUGGCCAUGAAGGCCUCGCUCUGCAAGCUGUCGCCCUGCACGGUGACUCGCGUGUGCGACUACCACACCAAGCUCUUCCUCAUCGCCAUCAGCUCCACCCUGAAGUCGCUGCUGCGCCCCCACUUUCUCAACACGCCUGACAAGAGCCCCGGCGACCGGCUGACCGAGAUCUGCACCAAGAUCACCGACGUCGACAUUGACAAGGUCAUGAUCAACCUCAAGACGGAGGAAUUUGUGCUGGACAUGAACACACUGCAGGCGCUGCAGCAGCUCUUGCAGUGGGUGGGCGACUUCGUGCUGUACCUGCUGGCCAGCCUACCCAACCAGGGUUCCCUGCUGAGGCCGGGCCACAGCUUUCUGCGGGACGGCACCUCGCUGGGCAUGCUUCGGGAAUUGAUGGUGGUCAUCCGCAUCUGGGGCCUUCUGAAGCCCAGCUGCCUGCCCGUGUAUACGGCCACUUCGGAUACCCAGGACAGCAUGUCCCUGCUCUUCCGCCUGCUCACCAAGCUCUGGAUCUGCUGUCGCGAUGAGGGCCCAGCGAGCGAGCCGGACGAGGCGCUGGUGGAUGAAUGCUGCCUGCUGCCCAGCCAGCUGCUUAUCCCCAGCCUGGACUGGCUGCCAGCCAGCGACGGCCUGGUCAGCCGCCUGCAGCCCAAGCAGCCCCUUCGUCUGCAGUUUGGCCGGGCGCCCACGCUGCCUGGCAGUGCUGCCACCCUGCAGCUCGACGGCCUCGCCAGGGCCCCAGGCCAGCCCAAGAUCGACCACCUGCGGAGGCUGCACCUUGGCGCUUGCCCCACGGAGGAAUGCAAGGCCUGCACCAGGUGCGGCUGUGUCACCAUGCUCAAGUCGCCCAACAGAACCACGGCGGUGAAGCAGUGGGAGCAGCGCUGGAUCAAGAAUUGCCUGGCUGUUGAAGGCCGUGGGCCGGACGCCUGCGUGACCAGCAGAGCUUCUGAGGAAGCCCCUGCCUUUGUCCAGCUGGGCCCGCAGUCCACACACCACUCUCCCAGGACCCCCAGAUCCCUGGACCAUCUGCAUCCAAAGGACCGUCCGUGACGGCCGGGGGUCCAGGCGGACCUUGUGGUGACCCGGCUCGGGCGUCUCCUCGGUUUCCUUGCCUCACCCACGGAGAGCGCUGAACCUGGACAAGCAGCGGCUGGGAAGGACAGGUCCAAUAAACGCCCUCUGCGCCCA